AUCUGGCCCCUGGGCAGCUGCCCGGGGAGGCGGCCAGCGAGCUGGGGCCGCGCAAUGUCGCACGGAGCCGGGCUCGUCCGCACCACGUGCAGCAGCGGCAGCGCGCUCGGACCCGGGGCCGGCGCGGCCCAGCCCAGCGCGAGCCCCUUGGAGGGGCUGCUGGACCUCAGCUACCCCCGCACCCACGCGGCCCUGCUGAAAGUGGCGCAAAUGGUCACCCUGCUGAUUGCCUUCAUCUGUGUGCGGAGCUCCCUGUGGACCAACUACAGCGCCUACAGCUACUUUGAAGUGGUCACCAUUUGCGACUUGAUAAUGAUCCUCGCCUUUUACCUGGUCCACCUCUUCCGCUUCUACCGCGUGCUCACCUGUAUCAGCUGGCCCCUGUCGGAACUUCUGCACUAUUUAAUCGGUACCCUGCUCCUCCUCAUCGCCUCCAUUGUGGCAGCUUCCAAGAGUUACAACCAGAGCGGACUGGUAGCCGGAGCGAUCUUUGGUUUCAUGGCCACCUUCCUCUGCAUGGCAAGCAUAUGGCUGUCCUAUAAGAUCUCGUGUGUAACCCAGUCCACAGAUGCAGCCGUCUGAUGAGGCCACAACCCCUAGGCCCCUCAGGAGCUUUGCAGAGAGGAGGACGUGUACUCCAGGCGAGGCCUCUGGACCUGUGUUCCUGUGCCAAAGUCCUGUCAGGCUGGUGGGCACCAGGAAAGGCCUGCACCCUCUUCCUGCUCUCCCAGGAAGCCAGCUCCCUGAGCUCCUGAGCCAGCCGGAAACUCUUCCUCCAGCCUUCCGGGGAGAACAUCCCUCCCAUUCUGGGAAAGGAAAGCAGCCUCCAGGGAAAUGUUUUCUGCCUUCCUGCUUCUAGAACCACCUCAGGUACUGAUGAACCCCACUUAGCACAGCUGAAGGGGUUUGUGAAUACUCCCGCCUAAAUCCCUUCUACUUCACUCCUCAGGGGAGUGAAGUGCCUUAAGAAACAAAGCCCUGUCCUAAUUUAUCUAGCUUGUCAGUCCGGUCUUAGAGAUACCCUCUUUCCUGAAGUGAGGCGUGCCUGUAGAAACACUAUGUGGUCAGCCUGUCCCCAAGGAGAUCUUGUGUCUCCUCUCCAUCUCUGCCUUUGUUACCAGUGUGCAUGUGUUUGUGUGUUUUUUAAUAAAAUAUUGACUCGGCCAGUUGCACAAGGAUUUCUUAUUGAACCAGAUGAAGGCUGUAAAACCUGGCCUGAAACAGUUUCCAUUCGAGCUUGUGUCUGGCCCAUGGCCCUCCACCCGUGCUCUGUGUGUGCCCCUUGCUGAACUGCUGGACUUCAGGUUUUCUCUCCAUCUUGGGGGAUAGUAUAGCAGGGCAGAGUUUUAGGUAAACAUGUGCAGGUUCUCAAUUAUAUUCACGUCCUCCUUCUCCUGCAAUACCAAUCUUCUCAUUUUGGAAAGAGCUUUAGAGCAAGCUAAGGGUUGUGUUUACACUAUGAUGAUUAAUGAUCUCGGCCUAAAUGUGCUGUUUCGCUGAUCUUGAGCUGCUCAGUUGGCUAGAAAAAGGAGGGAUGGAACAAUGUUUGAGCAACCCCGUGUGCAAGGACCUACAUUCACAACCACAUCUAAUAGCGAUGGUAGUGACUGCAAGGGGGCAGGUUAUAGGACCACAUUUUUAGAAAUGAAAUCGGGGCUCCAUCCCCAGGCACAGGGCAAGCCAGUGAGGAGCUGGGCUCAGGAUCUAGGUCUGCCUGACUCCCAGCCCCAUCCUUGCCUCUGCUGAGUGUUGCCGGAAAUGGAAGCAGCCCCUGUGGGCUUUGAGCUGGAGCUCUGGGGCUACUCUUGUGGCUGCUGGCCAGCUCGGGGCAUCGGGUUCUGUCUGGGAUGAUCUAA